GGGAUUAUAGGCGUGGGCCACAGCUCCUGGCCGAAUUUGAUUUUUAUUUAAUUUAAAUAACCAUAUGGGAGUAGACAGUGCGGCCCCCUAGAUUCUGCUCUUUUUAGUCCAUUUCUCCCCUUUGUCUUCCUGAAGGCUGAGUUGCUUAAUGUCUCUUGAGUACAUCUAGAAGUAGCUUGGGCCUUAUGUUCUGACACACAAUUCUUGGGAGACUGUCGUUGUACCCUAGAAACAUUAAAAGCUUUUAGUUAGGCAGCUGCAGUAGCUCACUCCUGUAAUCCCAGCACUUUGGGAGGCUGAGGCAGAAGGGUUGCUUGAGCCGAGGAGUUGAAGACCAGCCUAGGCAACGUGGGAAACCCCAUCUAUACAAAAAAUGUUUAAAACUUGAAGUAUCUCACAUUGUUCAGUUUGCAGACUUUCUUUCCCACUUAUUUUCAGUACUGUGCCACUCUCCAUCCUGAGUGUAAGCCUGUGUGGUUCAAACCUCCAGUUUUCUCGUGCAUAGGGGGAGAAGGGCUUUGUUCUGUGUUUUGUUUUAGCUGGCUGGUGUUUGAGUAGGAGUCAAGCUAACUGCUUUACUGGCUUUUAACCAGCCCUUCUCUUUUAGCGCCAUCUUUCAAUAUUGCCUUUUGUGGUACCUGGUUUUUACAGUCCCUUUAGUGGGAAUCAGCUUGCUUCUCAAUAACACACCUCACCCCAACCACUGUGCCCUUUGCAGGCUUUGAGUUUUAUCUUUUGGCUCUGCUAAGCAGUCAUCAAUCAUCAGUUUCUCCUUUAUGGCCUUAAAAAACUGGUUUGCAUAUCAUACCCUGUUUGCAUUUGUGUCGUCCUGGUUAAUUUAUCCUUUCUUAAAAAAAUGUCUCAGGUUGUGGGGGUCAUGUUCGUGGGUUUUAGGAAUGACUGGAGUGGAGAGAGAAAGAUACAUAUAUGUACUUCGUCCACUAUGUUUAUUAGAAUUCCUUCCAUUUAUUCAGCCUGCACCAGUCUGGCCUCUGACCCCACCACUUCAGGGAAACUGCUUUUUUAGGUCACCUGUCAUCCUCAUGUUGCCAAAUCUAGCGGCCGUUCUUCCCCCCAGUAGCACUUGACACUCAAUUGUUCCUUCCUUGAAACAUUGUUUUUCCAAGACACCACAUUCCCAUGUUUCCUCCUACUUUAUAAUCUUCCUUAACUGGCUUCUUUUACUCUGUUGUACUUUUAACAGUAGUGUCUCUGACUUUAGUCUUCAGCCCUCUUCUGUCAUUCUGUUCCUCAGGUGGUUUAAUCUGCUUUGAUGAUUUUAAGAAACAUGAGUAUUGGCCGGGCGCGGUGGCUCAUGCCUAUAAUCCGAGCACUUUGGGAGGCUGAGGCUGGCAGAUCACCAGGUCAGGGGAUCGAGACCAUCCUGGCUAACACAGUGAAACCCCGGCUGUACUAAAAAUACAAAAAAUUAGCCAGGCGUGGUGGCAGGCACCUGUAAUCCCAGCUACUCGGGAGGCUGAGGCAGGAGAAUGGCGUGAACCCGGGAGGCGGAGCUUGCAGUGAGCCGAGAUCGCGCCACUGCACUCCAGCCUGGGCAACAGAGCGAGACUCCAUCUCAAAAAAAAAAAAAAAGAAGCAUGACCAUUCUGAAGAUUCUUAAAGCUGUCUGUUUGUUUUCAUCUCCACUGCUACCACUCUUGCCUAGGUCUCUCUGACCUCUGGUCUGGACUCCCACAAUAGCCUCUACACUGGUCACCUAGCUUAUGCUCUUGCACCCCUACAGUGCAUUCCUAACAUAGAAGAAACUCCUUACCAAGGCCCAUAGGCCCUUUAAUAAUGGUGUCCUGUUCAUCAGUGAAACCCAUGCUCAUCAGGGACCUAUGCACUGAUUUCCUUCUGAGACUCUUCUUGGCUCUUUGCAUAGCCAGCUGCUUUUAAUCCUUCAUGCCUCAGCCCAAUUUUCACUCUUUAAAAGAGUACUUCCCUCACAAUUGUGUCUUAGUUGGUCCUCUUUGUCUCCUCAACCCCAAACAUCAUAAUCUAUAAUUUUUUUCAUGUAUUUGUUUAUUGACAUCUUACUUGCUAGAAUCUAAACUCUGAUACAUGGGGUCUUAUCUGUUUUUGCCUCUAGGGUGUCUUGUCUGCAUAACAGGUGCUUAAUAACUAUUAGUUGAACCCCCAUUUCCUCAUAAGUCAGAUGAAAAUAAAAGCACGUGCCUUACUUCACAAAGUAAUUAAGGGGAUAAGUUAUACUGAUGUACUUUAAAAACUAGGUGGUAGGGAGGCACAGUGGCUCAGUCCUGUUGUCCUGAUGCAUGAGGAGGUAAGGCCAGGCAUUCAAGACCAGUUUGGGCAACAUAGGAAGCCUUCAUCUAUAUAACAAAAAAAAAUUUUUUUUUUUAGUUUAAAAACUAGGUGGUAGUUUUCAAACUGAUACAAUGGAAUUAAAGAUAGGAAACAUGAAAAGAACAUAGGUGCUUAAUAAAUAUUUGUUGAAUACGCUAACAUGAUGGAAUUAGAGAUGGAAAACAAAAAUAAUGAAAGGGAUAGGAUAAAGUUUGCUCAGCCUUUUUGGAAACAUUAGUGAUGGCUCAUGAAGCAAUGGAAUAUGAUGUUCAGGUGCAGUUAAAUCAUGCCGAACAACAGCCAGCUCCUGCUGGCAUGGCCAGCAGCCAAGGGGGACCAGCCCUCCUCCAGCCUGUUCCUGCUGAUGUGGUCAGCAGCCAGGGGGUACCAUCCAUCCUCCAGCCAGCUCCUGCUGAGGUGAUCAGCAGCCAAGCGACACCACCCCUGCUCCAGCCUGCUCCGCAACUGUCUGUUGACCUGACAGAAGUGGAGGUCUUGGGAGAAGACACUGUGGAGAACAUCAAUCCAAGAACUUCAGAACAACAUAGGCAGGGAUCUGAUGGUAAUCACACCAUCCCAGCAUCUUCGUUGCAUUCAAUGACCAACUUCAUCAGCGGACUGCAGAGACUUCAUGGCAUGCUGGAAUUCCUGAGACCUUCAUCUUCAAACCACAGUGUAGGGCCAAUGAGAACAAGAAGGAGGGUAUCUGCUUCACGGAGGGCAAGAGCCGGAGGGUCUCAGAGGACAGACAGUGCCAGGUUGAGAGCACCAUUGGAUGCUUACUUUCAGGUGAGCAGGACCCAGCCUGACUUGCCAGCUACCACUUAUGAUUCAGAGACUAGGAAUCCUGUAUCUGAAGAGUUGCAGGUGUCUAGUAGUUCUGAUUCUGACAGUGACAGCUCUGCAGAGUAUGGAGGGGUUGUUGACCAGGCAGAGGAAUCUGGAGCUGUCAUUUUAGAAGAGCAACUAGCAGGUGUCUCAGCAGAGCAAGAAGUUACAUGUAUCGAUGGAGGCAAGACCCUCCCCAAACAGCCAUCUCCCCAGAAGUCUGAGCCUCUGCUACCUUCUGCUUCUAUGGAUGAGGAAGAAGGGGACACUUGUACAAUAUGUCUGGAACAGUGGACCAAUGCUGGGGACCACCGGCUCUCAGCAUUACGCUGUGGGCAUCUCUUUGGGUAUAGGUGCAUUUCCACGUGGCUUAAAGGACAAGUACGAAAAUGUCCCCAGUGCAACAAGAAAGCCAGGCACAGUGACAUUGUCGUCCUUUAUGCCCGAACCCUGAGAGCUUUGGACACUAGUGAACAGGAGCGCAUGAAAAGUUCCCUACUGAAGGAACAGAUGCUAAGGAAACAGGCCGAGUUAGAAUCAGCACAGUGCCGACUCCAACUGCAGGUCCUCACUGAUAAGUGCACUAGGCUUCAAAGGCGUGUUCAGGACUUGCAAAAACUUACGUCACAUCAAAGUCAGAAUUUACAGCAACCCAGGGGCUCCCAAGCAUGGGUCCUGAGCUGCUCACCCUCCAGCCAGGGCCAGCACAAGCACAAGUACCACUUCCAAAAGACCUUCACAGUAUCUCAGGCAGGAAACUGCCGGAUCAUGGCAUACUGUGAUGCUCUGAGCUGCCUGGUGAUAUCACAGCCUUCUCCUCAGGCCUCUUUUCUUCCAGGCUUUGGUGUUAAGAUGUUGAGUACUGCCAACAUGAAGAGCAGUCAGUACAUUCCGAUGCAUGGCAAACAGAUCCGUGGACUGGCGUUUAGCAGUUACCUCAGAGGCUUGCUACUCUCUGCUUCCCUAGACAACACUAUUAAACUGACCAGCCUGGAGACAAAUACCGUGGUCCAGACUUAUAAUGCUGGACGUCCUGUCUGGAGCUGUUGCUGGUGUCUUGAUGAGGCUAACUACAUCUAUGCUGGACUGGCCAAUGGUUCAAUUCUGGUAUAUGACGUGCGAAACACGAGCAGUCAUGUGCAGGAGUUAGUAGCUCAGAAAGCCAGAUGCCCACUGGUCUCCCUGUCAUACAUGCCCAGAGCUGCCUCAGCUGCAUUUCCAUAUGGUGGGGUGCUGGCUGGAACCUUGGAGGAUGCUUCAUUCUGGGAACAGAAAAUGGACUUUUCUCAUUGGCCUCAUGUGCUGCCCUUGGAGCCAGGGGGCUGCAUAGACUUUCAGACAGAGAACAGCUCCCGGCACUGUCUUGUGACCUACAGGCCUGAUAAAAAUCACACCACCAUACGAAGUGUGCUGAUGGAAAUGUCCUACCGACUGGAUGACACUGGAAAUCCAAUCUGCUCCUGCCAGCCUGUACAUACAUUUUUUGGAGGACCUACUUGCAAACUAUUGACCAAAAAUGCCAUUUUCCAAAGCCCAGAGAAUGAUGGCAACAUCCUGGUGUGUACUGGGGAUGAAGCAGCAAAUUCUGCCCUGCUGUGGGAUGCUGCCAGUGGCUCGUUGCUCCAGGACCUACAGACCGAUCAGCCUGUGUUGGACAUCUGCCCAUUUGAGGUGAACCGUAACAGCUACUUGGCUACCUUAACAGAGAAGAUGGUCCACAUCUAUAAGUGGGAGUGACUGUGGUCUCGAAACCUUGAAGGCAUGCUGCUGGUUAGAUGUUGUUUGCUAGCGCCUAGCAGCCCCAAGCAAGAUCCCUGUUUAUUGUCUGCAGUCUAGAACAUUGGGAAUCAUGGUUUGUUUGCAUUAGUAUGAUUCUAGGACCCUAGGUCACUGAGACACUACAGAUUGUGUAUCUGUUAUGUCCACUAAAAGAGUAAUUGAUGGGUACUUUAUCUACAUUAUCCAUUUCUUGGGUUUAAAGCCUUCAUUAACCAUUAUUGUAUGUUGGAAAUUCUUAUUUUCUUUAUUUUCUGUGUGACUUUCUGGACCUUAGAGAGUGUCCUCUCAUCAUCUAGGAUGUGAGUGGGCAUCAAGCAUUUUCUGGGGAAUAUGACAUCCCAUCUGAGUUGUCCUGUCACUUAAGUAUCCUUGAAGGGACUAACCAUCGUCUUGGUACUGAUUUGAUGCAACGUAGAUGUAAAAGAGUAUUAUUCAGUUGAACACAAGAGGGCACUGUAGAACCUUGUGUCCGGUUUAUUUCUGACCUUGAAGGCUGACAAUCUUUUAGUAACUUGUCUCAUCUCCACACAAGUGUGUGAUAGCACACCUGGGUGUGCUUUGUGGCAAUAACACUUGUGUUCCAGGUGUGAAGUGCUGGGACAUUGGCAGGCCCAGUGAUGGAAGCAGCUAGUGAACGAUUCCCUUUGCUAAUGCCUAGUGCAUUAAGUUCAUUGCUUUGCGAAAGGUAAGGAAAGAGGCCAGUUGUUUGAGCGGUGGGGAAGAUUUUGUUUUUUCUAGCCAGCUUAGGAUCUCAGGAUUGGUUUUAUCCAAGCUAGUGCUUUGAAGAACACUAUCUCUUGCCAGGAAAAGAUGAGUGAUAGGUCAAAGCUUUUACUUGAGUCUCCCCUAGUGUCAGAGAUCAGGAGAAAAGACAUAAGAGAAUUUACAAAAGCUAUUCAGACUGCUAUUGAAAACAUGAGAAGAACUUGUCUCCCAUUUUGAGAGUUCCUAUCUAAAUAAAGCCAAUUCCUCAGACUGAGGGGCUGUUCUUAAGUGUUCUUUAUACAUUCCAGUUAUCCAGUUAAAGCCUUCCCCAUGUGAAGCUGAUGUUUGAUUCCAGUUUCCUUUGAUUUGCCUCCCUAACCUUUUCUAGGGCUCAGUUUGUAUUUCUUUGCCUUGCCUCAGACUACUUUGCCAACCCACUUCCACAACAGAAUAUGCUUCAAGAUGUGGGCAGGUCAGUGUCCUGUUCAUGGGAGAAAAUGGCUUAACAGUCUGAUUUUCUCAAAUGAUUAUUGAAGAGUUGUUAUCGUUUUUAUUAUAAAACACUUCUGACCUGUCAAUUCAAGAGCUGUUUCUAGGAUCUUUCUCUCCGGCAAGGGGUUGUUGCACUAGAUUUCCCCAGAGUUCCAAGUUCUAGUUGUGCCUUUUAAUGACCCUUUAAUAUUUUAGGACAUAAUUUUUUCCUUUUUUAAAUUUUUUUGUAGAAAUAGAUGUUUCACUACGUUGUCCAGGCUGGUCUUGGACUCCUGGCCUCAAGCAAUCCUCCCACCUCAGCCUCCUAAAGUGCCAAAAUUAUAGGCGUGAGCCACUGCACCCGGCCCCUAUUUGAAGACGUCUUUUGUAAAAGCUAGCUUCUAGAACCUGAGAAAAGCUCUUUUCUCAGAGGAGAUACUCCUUUUGAUAUGUUAAUGAUUAAGAGUGGUUGCCCAGGCCUAGUUUCAGUGGCAGAAUAGGAUUGGAAUUAAAAAGCAGAACUCAUCUGGCUUCAGCAGAUUGCCACCAAGAGGAUACAGGUGGUCAGGUCCUGGCUGGCUUUGUCUUUGGGCCUGGGCAGGCUUAGGAUUUGACUUUCUUUGAAGUACCUGAUGCUGAUUGAUUCCACUAAUAGUAGGAAGCAAGAGACUUAACUAUGAGGGACGUUAUGUGAAUCUUAAGUCUUACCAGUCCUUGCAUUAGUACAUUAAAUUUGGAUGUUUUGGAAGCAAAUUCAUACGAUCGUGAGUGAUUUCUCCAAAGAAAAAAAGCCUUGUCCAGCCUGACCAACAUGGUGAAACCCCAUCUCUACUAAAAAUACAAAAAUUAACUGGGUGCAGUGGUGCGCAUGCCUGUAGUCCCAGCUACUUGGGAGGCUGAGGCAGGAGAAUUGCUUGAACCCUGGGAGGCAGAGGUUGCAGUGAGUCGAGAUCGCGCCACUGCACUCCAGCCUCGGUGACAGAGCAAGACUCCAUCUCAAAAAAAACAAACAAACAAAAAAAAACCCUGAUGCCAUUCCCAGUCCCCGUUGUAGGACAUCACAUUUAUAAAUCCAGGCUUUAGUCUUCUGGGCUCCACCAGUCUCUGCCCCACCAUAUUCCUUUGUCACUACCUCUAAGUUUUUUUCCCCACUUGAGGAUUUGGAGUUAAACGAACUCAAAAUGUCUUGUCAUUGUAUGUAUUCUUGCCCCUGCUUUGAAAACAGGGCCAUGGGAACUCUGUUUAUGCCCUGUUUUAAUGUUUCUGUUUUAUGUUUUACUGUUAAUAUGAAAAUAAAGAAUUUGCUAUGUA